GCCAGCGCCCGCAGGACCCGGAUGAGAGCGCACGCUUCGGGGUCUCCGGGAAGUCGCGGCGCCUUCGGAUGUGGCGGAUGCGGCCGUGAGCCGGCGGGGGAGGUGCGCCAGUGUCCUCCGAGCUCGCCCGCAGACUCCCCACCCCGUUCCGCGCCCUUUGCCCUUCCCCGCAUCCAGUCCUCCUUCCGUUGCUCCAGGAGCCCUCGGGCUGUUCCUCCUUUGGGAACGGGAAGGACUGCGGAGGCAUAGAGAGGGAAGGGAGACCGCGAUUCGUGCAUAUCCCAGACUAGAACCUUGCCUGCUUUCCUUUCACUGUCUCAGUUCCUCCAGAUCCAGCUGGUGCCCUCGCCUGACGUUUGAACGACCACCUGCUCACCUCCUCCCUUUUGCGCGUUGAUUCUUCAGACUUCAAAGGGCCCACCGGUCUGCUUGCCCAACGUUAUUAGUGCCCCUAUUGCUCUACAAAUUCGAACCUCAAACACAAAACCAGUAUUUCUCCGUAGGGAACCUUAAUGAGCCAGGAGAGCCGUCAGCCCUGCAGCCUCCAGGGUACCCCACAUCAAACAGGCUCCCCGGGAACAAGAGGAAUACCACGUGGCUUGGCACACUCGCAGAAUGCCAGAGAGGAGCCAACCCCCAUUUUACAGAUGAGGAAGCUGAGGCUUAGGGAGGAAUUGGUUUACCUAAGACCCUCCCCACAACCCCAAGUAGGCUGAGGCAGAGCUAUGUUGAUUCUUCCUAUUGUGCACCCACACAGAGGCCAACACGCUGCUGAACCAGGCUGAACUGAGGAAAAGCUAGAAAGUCAUCGUGGUUUACAUCUUGCCUUUCCCAUAGCAGAGACUCUGCCUGACUUUGGAGGCACUGAAUUAUCAGUAGUAAAAACACACUCUGUAGAAAAACUAGACAUUGGUUUAGAUUCUGGCUGUUACCUGUAUUACCUUGGACAAGUCCCUAGAGCUCUCUGAGUCUGUUUCCCAGAAGUAAAAUGGGUCACAAACCUGGCUAGCUCCCCCCAUUCCCUUCCCUUUUGGUGCCAAGGCCAGUGAGGGCAAGCGUGUGACGAGCUUUGUUAACUUUUUCGCUGCAUGUGAUGCCCGUGUAAAAGAUAGUUAUUCUGAGGAUCACUGUCCUUUAGUGAUGAAGUGGGUGCUGUUCCUGGACAUAAAGGCAGACCUGUGCUUGACAUGGAUUGAUCUGUCUUCUGGCAGUGAAGUGCAGGCAUGAACCUUGGUCAGCCCCACACUCUUCUCCAUCCGUAGCCCAUGUACUAGAGUUUGGACUUGGACCGAAGUCUGGGGCAGCUCCCUAAUUACUAGGGUGCUGAAGGCGUGAUUGUGCCAGUCGACUGCGAGUUCCUUCCGCAGCUUGUAUCGUUACCCACUCCUGCAGGUGCUGCUGCUGCCUCCACUGUACUCAGACCCAGGUAGCACAGGAUUGUCCAUCCUCCAGCAGCUCAGUGCAACGGUGUGAACUCAGCCUGUUUCAGAGCCUCCACACCAUGACCUCCAAGAAGCUGGUGAACUCGGUGGCUGGCUGUGCUGAUGACGCUCUUGCUGGCCUGGUGGCCUGCAACCCCAACCUGCAGCUCCUGCAGGGCCACCGCGUGGCCCUCCGUUCUGACCUGGACAGCCUCAAGGGCCGGGUGGCACUGCUGUCGGGUGGGGGCUCUGGCCAUGAGCCUGCCCAUGCUGGUUUCAUAGGGAAGGGGAUGCUGACUGGGGUCAUCGCGGGAGCUGUGUUCACCUCCCCGGCAGUGGGCAGCAUCCUGGCAGCCAUCAGGGCCGUGGCCCAGGCCGGCACAGUGGGGACGCUCCUUAUCGUGAAGAACUACACUGGGGAUCGGCUCAACUUCGGCCUGGCCCGGGAGCAGGCCCGGGCUGAAGGCAUCCCGGUGGAGAUGGUGGUGAUUGGGGACGACAGCGCCUUCACUGUCCUGAAGAAGGCAGGCCGGCGGGGGCUGUGCGGCACGGUGCUUAUACACAAGGUGGCAGGUGCUCUGGCUGAGGCUGGUGUGGGGCUGGAGGAGAUCGCAAAGCAGGUGAACGUGGUCGCCAAGGCCAUGGGUACCCUGGGGGUGAGCUUAUCCUCCUGCAGCGUCCCUGGUUCCAAACCCACCUUCGAGCUCUCAGCCGACGAGGUGGAGCUGGGCCUGGGGAUCCACGGGGAAGCUGGUGUGCGCCGGAUAAAGAUGGCAACCGCCGAUGAGAUUGUGAAACUCAUGCUCGACCACAUGACAAACACCACCAACGCGUCCCAUGUGCCUGUGCAGCCCGGCUCCUCAGUUGUGAUGAUGGUCAACAACCUGGGUGGCCUGUCAUUCCUGGAACUGGGCAUCAUAGCCGACGCUACCGUCCGCUCCCUGGAGGGCCGCGGGGUGAAGAUUGCCCGUGCCCUGGUGGGCACCUUCAUGUCAGCACUGGAGAUGCCUGGCAUUUCUCUCACCCUCCUGCUGGUGGAUGAGCCUCUCCUGAAACUGAUAGAUGCUGAAACCACUGCAGCAGCCUGGCCUAACGUGGCUGCAGUCUCCAUUACUGGGCGGAAGCGGAGCCGGGUAGCCCCUGCCGAGCCCCAGGAGGCCCCUGAUUCCACUGCUGCAGGAGGCUCAGCCUCGAAGCGGAUGGCGCUGGUGCUGGAACGGGUGUGCAGCACUCUCCUGGGCCUGGAGGAACACCUGAAUGCCCUGGACCGGGCUGCUGGUGACGGCGACUGUGGCACCACCCACAGCCGUGCGGCCAGAGCAAUCCAGGAGUGGCUGAAGGAGGGCCCACCCCCUGCCAGCCCUGCCCAGCUGCUCUCCAAGUUGUCUGUCCUGCUCCUGGAGAAGAUGGGAGGCUCAUCUGGGGCGCUCUAUGGCCUGUUCCUGACUGCGGCUGCACAGCCCCUGAAGGCCAAGACCAGCCUCCCAGCCUGGUCUGCUGCCAUGGAUGCCGGCCUGGAAGCCAUGCAGAAGUAUGGCAAGGCUGCUCCAGGGGACAGGACUAUGCUGGAUUCUCUGUGGGCAGCGGGGCAGGAGCUCCAAGCCUGGAAGAGCCCAGGAGCUGAUCUGUUACAAGUCCUGACCAAAGCAGUCAAGAGUGCCGAAGCUGCAGCCGAGGCCACCAAGAAUAUGGAAGCUGGAGCCGGAAGAGCCAGUUAUAUCAGCUCAGCACGGCUGGAGCAGCCAGACCCCGGGGCGGUGGCAGCUGCUGCCAUCCUCCGGGCCAUCUUGGAGGUCUUGCAGAGCUAGGGUGUGUGACUGCCUCCCUUGGCCUCAGCUCCUCUCACUGCUGUGCUGAGGUGGCCUUUGUCACUUCCUUCUGCCUUCCAACCCUCACCUUCCCCCGGCCUGGCCCCAUUGGCCCACCCUCUAAGUUGAGCAGGAAAUCCUCCACCAAGCUUCCAGAACUACAGACAGCACCCAGAGUGAGCUGGAGUGGGUCCCCAUGCCUCUCCAGCAUGCCCUUUCCCUUUGCAGGAGGGUGGAGUCCCUGGGUCAUGCCCUCCCCUGCCAGCUCUGGGCUUCAGAGAUAAGGCAUUUUCCUUGUGCAGCCUUUACCUGGCAAUCCUAAUUUGGUUUUAAGACUCCCUGUGAAAUGCUUUCCGCACCUUAACCCCAGUGAGCGUGAAAAAGAAAGUUAAUAAACUAUAAUACAUGGAAGCAAGAAAGACACUGCCUCCUCUGAGGGACCUUUUCCCAAGCAUGUAAACAAGGGGGCCCACAGCCCUGGCUGCAGGCAUCAUGACCCAUCUUCUACCAGGCAGAUCUUUAUUACCUGAGCCCCUAAGGCAGUGUCUCCUCAGCUGGGCUGCUUCCACUGAGACCCCCGACCCAUCCCCUUUCCAGUACACACACCUGAUGCAUGUAAGAAUGGUAGAGGGGCUUUUCUUAGCAUUGAAUUAAUAAUUCAGUGGCUCCUCGGGAGUCGAAUGGGCAUUUGGGACACCAGAAGGAAAAGAAAUCAUCAUAGUCUAAGGUUCAGUUGUAGAUCAAAAAAUGCAGCCAGGCCGGGCACGGUGGCUCACACCUGCAAUCCCAGCACUUUGGGAGGCCAAGGCAGGCGGAUCCCUUACACUCAGGAGUUCAAGACCAGUCUGGGCAACAUGGUAAAACCCUGUCUCUACCAAAAAAUACAAAAUUAGCCAGGCAUAGUAGUGUGUGCCUAUAGUCCUAACUUGGGAGGCUGAGUUGGGAGGAUGGCUUGGGCCCAGGAGGUCGAGGCUGCGGUGAGCCAUAAGCAUGCCACUAUACUCCAGCCUGGGCAACAAAGCGAGACCCUGUCUCAAAAAAAAAAAAAAAAAAAAAAGAAACUGCAGCCAAGCCAGCCCCUAGGUCUCUUUCUAGAGCGAUCACUGAUGGCACCAGGGUGAGCAGGGGCACUGUAUGCAUGUGGAGACAAACAGCACAUGCCUGGCACACAUGUAGGGUAGGGAGUGGUUAAAGGCACUGGCUGUCGACUCAUACACAUGAUCUGAAAUCUGAUUCUGCUUUAACCCGGCUACAGGAGCUAAGGCCUAUUUUUUAGCCCUUUGGGAUCUGUAAAAUCAGAAUGGUACCCACCUCAUGGGGACAUGAAAGGAUUCAAAUGAAUUGAUGAAGAUGGGCCAUAAAGCCCAGCACAGUCCAAGUGCUCACUCACUGAGAGUUACGGUUAUCACAGGGGUUGGGCCCCCAGCCCCUCCCAGGUCAUCUGCUCUACCACUAGCUGGUAGGAAAGAGCCUCCUGCCCUCCCAACCCCCGUCACCUACUUGGCCCAAAUUUGGCUGCAGGCUCCCCGAGUGCCUGGGCUUCUCUACCCAGGGUCCUGUCUGUCGGCUGCACCAUACGUCCCUGACCACAAGGCAUCCACGUGCACAGGAGUAUGCGCCCAGCAGCUGGGAAGGAGGCUGACCUCAGACGGUGGCCUGUGGAUCCCAGCUCUGUCAUUUCCUGGCUGGGUGACCUCAACCUAGUCACCCUUUUUGAGUCUUGUUUUCUCAGAUUAUGAAAUAGGAAAAAUUUCCUUCCUCGUGAGAUAAGCACGUGCCAUUAGCUAUUAAGGACACGCACAUAAAUGAGCUGCAUGUGAAUCCACACAUGCCAUUCCAUGAAGACAGAGGAUCAUGUGGAUCUUUGGUGCCUUCCGGUUGGCCCCUCCCUAGGUCUGUGAGGGUCAGACCUGUCCUGAGGCUUUUACAAAUUGGCCCAGAACUCAUUUAACCACAGCAUCAUUUCAUUAGAGGGCUGUUAUUAGAGACUGAAUGUUUGUGUCCCCCCCAAAUUCCUGUGUUGAAAGGCUCACCCCCACUAUGGUAGUGUUAGGACGUGGGGCCUUUGGGAGGUGAUGGGGUUAUGAGGGUGGAGCCCCAGAGAGCUCUCACGCCCUUUCCACCAUGUGAGGUUAUGGUGAGAAGAUGGUCUCUGAGGAAGCUGGCCCUUGCCACACACCACAUUUGCCAGCGCCUUCAUCUUGGAUGUCUAUAGCCUCCAGAACUGUGAGAAAUAAACACUUGUUGUUUAAGCCACCCAGGCUAUUAUAUUUUUGUUAUAGCAGCCUGAACAAAGACAGCUUUGAUUCUUAACAUAUUUAAUGAAACUCGAGCUUCAUAAACCAGUGAAAUGCCUACCCCUAUGGAGAUGGGGAGCUGGUCAUGGGACCCAGGUGCCUGGAGGACAUCCCAGUGGCUUUGAAGGCUCCAGCCAGUCAAGACGGUCAAUAUUAGCCCUUCUGCCAACAUCUGGCAAUGUGAGGCUGGGGUGGACGUUGGCCUGAUGUUGCCAGGAGUAGGAUGCUGAUGCUGCCAGAGAGUAGGUGGGCUCCAAACCCCAGGCUUCUCACUUGCUUACUAAGCACAGCAGUCUGAAGCUUGGGACCUGGCAGUGCGUCUUUGGAGAAGGCAAAAAAGCCACAGCAGCAACACUUAGGAGCAAGACCCUUCCCGCUCUCCACCCUAUUUCCUCCCCUGAAGAAGAGCAACAGCUCAAGCUCUAGCAUGGCACAGAACGCU